GGCAGCCGAGCGCCGGAGGCCGUGGAGAGGGCGGGCAGGGAGGCGGCGGGCGCCGAGGAGACGCAGCGGCGGCGGUGGUGGCGGUGGUGGCGGCGGUGGCGGCGGCGGCGCCUGGUCUCGGCCGCAGCCUCUGCGUCCCGCCCGCUCUGGGUCGCCCCUGCCAGCCCCGCGCGCGGCUCGCCUCCCGCCGCGGCCCGCAGCCUGCGGCGCCCGAGCUCCGAGGGCGCUUCCCCGGGCGCUGGGCCCGAGGCGGCCAAGACGGCGGGCCGGCCGGGCACGGGGCGGCGGGCGCUGUGCUGCGGGCUGCGCUGGUGGGGGGCGGCGGGCCGCGGCGCGGGCCCAGGGCCCGGCGUGUGCGGCUGGGAGGCACUGUGGGGGCGGGCGCGCGGGCGGCGGCCGGGGCCAUGGCCGAGGGCGGCGGGGGCGCGCGGAGGAGGGCGCCGGCGCUGCUCGAGGCUGCCCGCGCGCGCUACGAGAGCCUGCACAUCUCGGACGACGUGUUCGGCGAGUCCGGCCCGGACAGCGGCGGGAACCCCUUCUACAGCACCUCGGCCGCCUCGCGCUCCUCCUCGGCCGCCUCCUCGGACGACGAGCGCGAGCCCCCGGGACCCCCAGGGGCCGCCCCGCCACCGCCCCGCGCCCCGGACGCACAGGAGCCGGAGGAGGACGAGGCCGGCGCGGGCUGGAGCGCAGCGCUGCGGGACCGCCCGCCCCCGCGCUUCGAGGAUACCGGCGGUCCCACCCGAAAGAUGCCCCCCAGCGCCAGUGCCGUGGACUUCUUCCAGCUCUUUGUCCCAGACAACGUCCUCAAGAACAUGGUGGUGCAGACAAACAUGUAUGCCAAGAAGUUCCAGGAGCGGUUUGGGAGCGACGGAGCCUGGGUGGAGGUGACGCUGACGGAGAUGAAGGCGUUCCUGGGCUACAUGAUCUCCACCAGCAUCUCCCACUGCGAGUCCGUCCUCAGCAUCUGGAGCGGAGGCUUCUACAGCAACCGCAGCCUCGCCCUCGUCAUGAGCCAGGCCCGCUUCGAGAAGAUCCUCAAGUACUUCCACGUCGUGGCCUUCCGCUCCAGCCAGACCACGCACGGGCUCUACAAGGUCCAGCCCUUCCUCGACUCCCUGCAGAACAGCUUCGACUCUGCCUUCAGGCCUUCCCAAACCCAGGUGCUACAUGAACCCCUGAUCGAUGAGGAUCCUGUAUUCAUUGCCACGUGCACAGAGCGGGAGCUGCGAAAGAGGAAAAAGCGGAAAUUCAGCCUCUGGGUCAGACAAUGUUCUUCCACUGGCUUCAUCAUCCAGAUUUAUGUCCACCUGAAGGAAGGUGGGGGCCCAGAUGGCCUGGAUGCGCUGAAGAAUAAGCCCCAGCUCCACAGCAUGGUGGCCAGGAGCCUGUGCCGGAACGCGGCAGGCAAGAACUACAUCAUUUUCACGGGGCCCAGCAUCACCAGCCUGACGCUGUUUGAAGAGUUUGAGAAGCAAGGGAUUUACUGCUGCGGCUUGCUCCGCGCGCGGAAGAGUGACUGCACCGGCCUCCCACUGUCCAUGCUGACCAACCCAGCCACACCCCCGGCCCGGGGCCAGUACCAAAUCAAGAUGAAGGGGAACAUGUCCUUGAUCUGCUGGUACAACAAAGGACACUUCCGCUUCCUGACCAACGCCUACUCCCCGGUGCAGCAGGGAGUCAUCAUCAAAAGGAAGAGUGGGGAGAUCCCAUGCCCCUUGGCCGUGGAGGCGUUUGCCGCUCACCUGAGCUACAUCUGCAGAUACGAUGACAAAUACAGCAAGUAUUUCAUUUCUCAUAAACCAAACAAGACCUGGCAGCAGGUGUUCUGGUUCGCCAUCAGCAUCGCCAUCAACAAUGCCUACAUCCUGUACAAAAUGUCAGACGCCUACCACGUGAAGAGGUACAGCCGGGCGCAGUUUGGAGAGAGACUCGUCAGAGAGCUGCUGGGCUUGGAGGAUGCCUCUCCGACCCACUGAUGCUGGGGGCGCAGGACUCGGUCAAGGGAGGGGCAAGAGGAGGAGGAGAGCCUGCCGUUCCAACUUGCCCAUCAGAGACCCGGACACGGCCUGGUGUGUGGCUUGCUGCCUGGGAGGGAUGCACAGGGCCUCUGGAGGGACAGGAUGGACCUGGUCAGAGGACGGUUGCUGUCCUCAUUUGCAUUCCAAGAAGAGCAUGUCCUCCCUCGAGAAACAGUGCCGCCGGUGUGAUGAGCACUUACACCCACGUUCUCAAGGGCAGAUUCUCUCAUGACAUCCGUGGAGCUUGCGAGGCAGCGUGGACUGGUGACUGUGAAGGAAGGCCCCCGUGGUAGAAUGAGCUGGAGCACGCUCUAAGAGAGAUGCCUGCUUCCUAAAGAUCUACAGCAAUCUGGGACGUGGUUCAAGUUCAAGACUUGAAGGAAGCAAAGACGCCCUGCAUGGUUACAAUGGCUCAGGUGUCAGGGGAGGCCGGAGGGUUUUCCAGCAUUUGCCUCAUGCCAGCACCUUUGAACCGGUCUCUUAGAAGAAGACACACAUCCUGGGUGUACAGUGGUGAAAUGGGGAGUGGGUGCCCAUUCUGAAAAACGAGGCAUUCCUGCUCAUUCCCUCUGCUUAGCUGGUGGGCAGGGGAGAGAGGGAAAUGCCAAAAACUUGGAGUGAAGGAUGAUGCUAUUUUUUAUUUUUAAAUAUAUCUUCAGGUUAUUUUCUUACUGUUGCUUCAGAUCUAAUGUAAAAGGCAGAUGUCCCCUCCUCUCCACCCCCGACGCUGACCCCGGCCUCAGUCACGGCUCUUUGCAUGAUCACAGUUCUGUGUUCUGGCCUGUGGCAGGGCCGGGAAGGGCCGCUGGCUUCCGAACAGACGUGGUUGCUCUCCACGAGGCGCAUGGGGAGCCCGCGGGCCCUAAGCUUUGUCGCAGAUGUCAUCAUUGGCAGAAUUACUUGUCUUGAAAAAUAAGUAGCAUUGCUGAAACACACAACCGAAUUCUCUACGAUGGCCAUUUGCUCAUUGUCUUUCCUCUGUGUGUAGUGAGUGACCCUGGCAGUGUUUGCCUGCUCAGAGUGGCCCCUCAGAACAACAGGGCUGGCCUUGGAAAAACCCCAAAACAGGACUGUGGUGACAACUCUGGUCAGGUGUGAUUUGACAUGAGGGCCGGAGGCGGUUGCUGACGGCAGGACUGGAGAGGCUGCGUGCCCGGCACUGGCAGCGAGGCUCGUGUGUCCCCCAGGCAGAUCUGGGCACUUUCCCAACCCAGGUUUAUGCGUCUCCAGGGAAGCCUCGGUGCCAGAGUGGUGGGCAGAUCUGACCAUCCCCACAGACCAGAAACAAGGAAUUUCUGGGAUUACCCAGUCCCCCUUCAACCCAGUUGAUGUAACCACCUCAUUUUUUACAAAUACAGAAUCUAUUCUACUCAGGCUAUGGGCCUCGUCCUCACUCAGUUAUUGCGAGUGUUGCUGUCCGCAUGCUCCGGGCCCCACGUGGCUCCUGUGCUCUAGAUCAUGGUGACUCCCCCGCCCUGUGGUUGGAAUCGAUGCCACGGAUUGCAGGCCAAAUUUCAGAUCGUGUUUCCAAACACCCUUGCUGUGCCCUUUAAUGGGAUUGAAAGCACUUUUACCACAUGGAGAAAUAUAUUUUUAAUUUGUGAUGCUUUUCUACAAGGUCCACUAUUUCUGAGUUUAAUGUGUUUCCAACACUUAAGGAGACUCUAAUGAAAGCUGAUGAAUUUUCUUUUCUGUCCAAACAAGUAAAAUAAAAAUAAAAGUCUAUUUAGAUGUUGAUUCUCCGUUAAUACGUGAAUUCGUUUAAAAGGUCAGGGAACAGGCGGGGUGCGGUGGCUCAUGCCUGUAAUCCCAGCACUUUUGGAGGCUGAAGCGGGCGGAUCGCUUGAGUCCAGGAGUUUGAGACCAGCAUUGGCAACAUGGCGAAAGCCCAUUUCUACAAAAAAUACAAGAAUUAGGUGUGGUGGCACAUGCCUGCAGUCCCAGCUACUUGGGAGGCUGAGGUGGGAGGAUCUCUUGAGCCACUGCACUCCAGCCUGGGUGACAGAGCCAGACCCUGUAUCAAGAAAAAAAACAAGGUGAAGGAACAAAAAUACAGGCUACUCUUUUAAAUACUUGAUUUUUUUUGUUAUAUAAUCUGGUGUGUAUGAUAUUAACUGUUCUUGGUGUCUCAAACCACUGAGCAGUUUAAAAAAGAAAUGUUUUUGAGUUUGGCUAAUAGAAAUACCUCUUGAUGUUGCAGUUGUAUGAGUGCAGUUGUAUUUGAGGUGCCUGUUUCAUUGAAGACACUAGCAGGCCUGCCUUCCGGCCUGGUGGUUUUCCCUCUUUUCUUCUAGUUUGUGUCGUGUGUCAUUCCAGAUGAGCAGGAAGAGGUGCUGUUCUGACAGGCAGUGGGUGGCUGCAUUCCCCAGUCAUGAGAGAAUAAUUGUAACAUUGUAACACUCUGUUUCUAAAAUGGCAGCCACCUGUUGUCUGAUACAUGAUGGGAAAAGGCAGCUGUUGAGCCGGGUCUAGGGGAGGCUUCAGUGGCCACUUCAGGUCUCUGGAGGAAUGCUGUUGACUGAGAAGAGUUUCUCUUCUCCAUCCAGAAGGACAGAAUAGCAUGUAGGACGGACUGACAGAACCUCCAGGGACCUGGACCUUGCCUUAGAGAUGUGAUUCAAAGUGGCUUUUUGGAGUGACUCUAGUUGAAGUGCAUCUGGUUCCAGUAUCUCCCUGGGUUCAACAGCCCUCAGGUUGAUUCUUGAUUGGCUUUGGAGUAGCUGGCCAUCCCUGGGGAUGAGGAAAGAGCAUCGUAAGUGGUCUUAUGACAGAGGGAGCCAGCAUGGCCCUGGCUGAGUAUAUGGGGCUGGCAAGCACCACUGCACACAUGGCAAGUGAGAGCCCAUUCCACUCAGAUCCAGCCACUAAGCCAAGCCGAUCCCCUGAGGGAUGUCUCUGCUGCAGGCUCUGGAAAAAAAAGAUGGAGCAAUGAGCUUCCCAGCCUUAUGCAAAACAAAACACCCACAAAAACUUCCAAGCUUCUCCAAAGAGAAUCUGCAUUUCCCUGCAACUCACAGGGAAUUGAACCUGCACUGAGCUUCACGGAGUUUAUGAGACCUUCCCAUUACUGCAGUUGUGUUGAGCGUCCCGUGAGGUCCUUCUUAGGCAAAUUUAACUUCAUUGAGUGAAUGUCUGUUUCUGUUUGGUGCCUACUUGAUCAGGUUCCAUAUUCGACUUUCAUUGUCUUUCCCCACACUCUGCUCCCUAAAGAGCCUCGAUUUUGGCCAGGUGCGGUGGCUCACACCUGUAAUCCCAGCACUUUGGGAGGCCGAGGCAGGCGGAUCACAAGGCCAGGAGAUUGAGACCAGCCUGGCCAAUAUGGUGAAACCCCAUCUCUACUAAAAAUACAAAAAUUAGCUGGGUGUGGUGGUGGACACCUGUAGUCCCAGCUACUCGGGAGGCUAAGCAGGAGAAUAUCUUGAAUCCGGGAAGCAGAGGCUGCAGUGAGCCAAGAUCGCACCACUGCACUCCAGCCUGGGUGACAGAGCGAGACUCCAACCCCCACCCCGCCACAAAAAAAAAAAAAAAAAAAAAGCCUCGAGUUUGAACAACGUCUUCCCGUGGUCCAUGGGACAUUAUACUAGGGACAUCUUUCAAAAGUCAGGCAAGUCAUAUGGAAAAGUCUUGGUGGCUGGGUCAUUCUGAGCAAACACAUCCAGUACUGACUAAAUCAGAUGAGGCUUGGUCACCAAAAUUGAGUUAACUCUGCUGCGUGCAAGAAGCAAGAAGAUUGCAGGUCCCCAGGACAGAGCCUGGAAGGUUCUGAAUCCUUCCUGUGUGGCCCGUGUGUCACCAUCCUCCCCAGGGACCCAGGCUCAGCCCCCCCAACAGUGAGGGGGGGUCACCAAGCAUCAGGCUGAGAGGAAGCAGGGCAAACCCGGGAGGGCCAUGGGGCCUUGCAACUACGCAAGCCUCACACAUUCUCCUCCAGUCUGCAUUCAUGGCAAAAAAAAAACAUUUCCCCACUUGCCUGGGAUUGGGGCGAGAACAAGUCAACGACACUGAUGGGGGAGAAAGGUGACCUUGGGUGUGGUACCUCCCAGAUCUGUCUCCUGCAUCCUCGCAGGUGCUGUGUUUGAAAGGUAUGACAGCGGUGGCUAACAGGCAGGCACACUUCCAGGCGGCUUGGGGUGGCCCUUCUGCCCCAGAGCCUUACUCCUCACAGGGAUCCCUGUGGGUUAGGCAUGGACUGUCACCACGCCCAGAUGGAGUGGUGCAAUGGUUCGCCCAGGUAAGCAGACCCGGGUUUGCCUGACGCAGGAGGCCGCGUCCUAACUGCUGUGGGCACUGGCUGUCCUGAUUCAUCACGAGGACGGGGGAUUUUAUCCCUGACUUACCUGACAACUUUGUGGGGGAUUUUCUCCUUUCCAUAUCCAAUCCUCUCUGCUGAUCCGAAUACUGAAAACAAUCAUUAUGAGAUCCGGGACAUCACCCUCCCCCUGGGUCCUUUUCUUGUCCUAGAUGGAGAUGGGUGUUUUGGAGCUUAACAACUACUGAAGCUGAAGUUAGCCUGGUAGGGAGCCACUAUUCUGGGGGGCAUUUGGACAGGGCAAGCCCUUGGCCACACCAGACCCUGAGCCAGAAAGAACCAUAGCGAUUUCCUCACCCAGAUGGCCCCAGCUCACAGUAUGGGGAGAGUGGGAUGGGGUGGGGGAGUGGAGCCAGCUGUGGGGUCUCAUCAGAGUGCCCUGGGAUCUAGGCCAGAGGCGCCGUCUUCACCCACAUGCCAGCUUUGUGGUUCUGGUCCCUCUUCCUUAAGCGAGGGCUUGCCAAGCUUUGGCUGUGGAAAGCCUUAGCCUUGUGUAGUGGGAGUUCCAAACGAAAGAAGUCCCCAGAAGUUCACAAGGUAGUGGCCAGGGAAAGUGUCCCCAGUGCCCCCUCCCCACCGGUGGCCUCUGCAGCUUGCUUUGGAAAACAGUUCUGUCUGUGAAGAAAUCUCUCCUGUUACGGCCCUGUGUCAGUCAAUGCGGGCUUGGCUGUCUGCCCAAAUACCUUCCGUUCUUAUCAGGAACAUGACUGAGGCUUCUCACUUUUGACUCCAUCACUUAAUCCCUUUUUCUCCGUGGCUUCUGUGUGUCUCAUCUUCGAGAAUAUUUCUCAGCCUUCUUUGCAGGUAUGUUAUUCUCUCCCAAUAAGAAAUAAAGAGUAUCAGGUACCAAAGUGGCACUUAGAGCUGUUGCCAUAAAAUAGCACCAGAGAGUAAGCAUGCCCUCUGGCCACGCAGCUCGCUGCCAUUUAGCCAUCUCUGUGUCCCUCCCUCCCUGGGGUGCCCAGUGCGCACCCCAGUUCUCCAGCAGCCCAGGCACAUUCUCCUAGCUCUGACCCCUGUCUGGUGGGGGCCGGGCAGCCUCUCUUGAGUGUAGGGCGGUGGUGCUGGCGCUGGUGGCAGCUCUGUGUGAACUGUGUUCCGGGGAGGGUGGGGCACCUUCACCCUUCCGUGUAUACCCAUGUAUACACGGUCGUAAUGAGGAGACUCCUGCGGGAGACUUGAUUGUGCGCUCCAUGUCACUAGCUACUCUACAAGCAGAUACUAUUCUUCAGGUUUUUUCCUUAGUUGCCUGGAAGCUUGACCUUGUGUGCAUGUAUUUGGAGAUGAAAACAGAAAGGGCGGGGAGGACAUCGGCUUGUGUGAAAGACCUAGGAAGACGAUGGAGGAGUGUGUGCGGCUUCCCUCACGUGUCAAGCCUCCUGGCUCCCUCAGGUGGAAGGGGCACUUUAUGGCCAAGGAAAUUCAGUGAGGAGUGAAGGGUGAGGCUGAGCCCGCCAGAUAAAUCAGCCUCGGCCCUCCCCUCCCCAAGGGUCAGCCCCCGGCAGCGCACCUCUGUUCUUGGUGCGUCUCGCUAGUCUUUGAUUCAUUCUUCUGCCGUCUUCACCCAAGCCUCGCUGGACUAAAGAGUGACAGUUAAUGCACAUGGAGCAUUUCUGUUCCAGCAGGUCACGUCUCCCUGUAUGGUUCCUUUGCUGAGUCCUCAGCAUUGCCCUGGGAGCUGACAACCAUCGGUCCCCCUUUUGUGAUGGGAAAGUGACACUCUGAGAGCCGUGGUGACUCUACAGGGUGUGGAGCCAGGUUGACCCUCACUCUGUCUGCUCCAGGGCUUCCUGGUUCUCAGCCACUGCUGCUUCUGAACUGCUACAGGCCAGGCAUUGUGCUAAGAACUGGGCACGUGUUACCCCAACGUGGUCUGUGCCCUUGAGGGUGCCAUGACUGAAACACGUUGGGGGCACAGAGCAGGCUGAUUCUCCGCCGAAAGAAGGCUCCAGCCAGAGGCCGAGACCCCGUGUGGGGGAGGUGGCAGUCACCAUUGCUGCUGGACUCAGCAACCCCCAGACCCUCCACCUUGCUUGGCAGGCAUCACAUGCACCUGGCUUAGCACAUCCCUGCAAACACAAGAGUCUGAGCCUCCUCAAGAGGCUGCAGUCACACUGCAUUUGACCAGGACUUGCCAACCUGCAACUUGCCCUGAGAGCCAGGUAUGCGUGUGUGUAUCUGGGGAGCACGCCCCAAACAUGAGCAGGGACGGUGUUCCCAGCUAUCCGAGAGGUCAUGCCCAAGCCAAAAGGAAGGCUCUAGCUCUUAAACAUGAAUAAGUUUAUUCCUUUCAUUUCCACAGUGUCUUAUGCUUGCUUCUGUUUUCUCCAAGGAAGUAUGGUGCCCACCUACUCCUCCAGCCUGACGAUCCAUGUGAGGGUUCCUUGUUCCCAGCCCAAUUCUCAUGUCCCACCUUUCUCCACUAAGAAACAGCCAAAUUUUGGCAAGAGUCGUGGUAGGAAAAAAAAACAAUAAUUGGGCAGAUGAGGAUUUUUCACUUUUUGACUAGUUCUUUCUCUAGACUUUCCUGUCUUUUUAAAACUUCUAGUUUCCCCCUUGAGCGCUCCCUCCCAGUGGGUAGACCACGGAAGGAAUGAACAGGGGAUGGAAGCAGGGGAUGCAGUCCCUAUUAUUUCAAUAGAUUGGAAAGAUGGGCCCAGAACAAUUGCGUACGGUGUUCAGUGUAAAUUGAAGAUCUGGAGUUGCAGGAUUGUUGAGGCAAUUUUUAGUUGCUUUGCUCCAUCUAAACACAAGGCCAUAGGAUAGUGUGACUUUGUAGCUUCAUCACCGUAUCCACAUCAGAAGUACAAUGUCCACUUAAUACAUAUAUACACAUAUGUACGUAUACACAUAUACACAUGUGUACAUAUGUAUGUAUACACAUGCACAUGUGUACGUAUGUAUGUAUACACAUACAUAUAUGUGUACACAUAUACAUAUGUAUGUAUACACAUAGAUAUAUGUGUACACAUAAACAUAUGUAUGUAUACACAUAAACAUGUAUGUAUACACAUACAUAUAUGUGUACACAUAUACUUAUGUAUGUAUACACAUACAUAUAUGUGUACACAUAUACUUAUGUAUGUAUACACAUACAUAUAUGUGUACACAUAUACUUAUGUAUGUAUACACAUACAUAUAUGUGUACACAUAUACACAUAUACAUAUAUGUGUACACAUAAAUAUGUAUGUAUCCAUAUAUGUAUAUAUAUACACAUGUAUACAGAUAUGCAUCUAUAUGUAUACCUCUAUAUGUAUGCACAUAUACAUAUAUGUAUACAUAUAUACAUAUAUGCAUACAUCUAUAAUAUAUGUAUGUGUAUAUAUACACAUACAGUGUCCACUUAAUAUAUAUAUCUAUCUUGUGUGUAUGUGUGUGUAAAUAUACACACACAUACACACACGAUAAAAUACAGAGUCUACCACAUGAUGAGCCUCUGCUAGGUCCUUAGCAAUCAAACCACAUGUCCAGUCCUGGCCCCCAUUCUACAACUAAACACAUGGGCCAGUUUAGGGGUCCAGGAGGGCAAGAAUGGUGGGUCCACGUAGAAACCAGGUGAGGGAGGAGCAGUCCACAGGGCUGGGGUGAUGGGCUGGUGAAGCAGUGUUCCAGGAGGGGAACUGCUGCUCACAGGGCUGUCCUGGUCGCCCUCGGGAUACAGCCAGACUUGAUCCGAGUGGCUCCCGGGGCUGAAUGGGGACCGCCGGGUGCAUAUCCCAGGAGGCAGCCUUCAGCUCAGUGGGGAAAGCAGUUUCCAACCUUAGAGCUGCCCAACACUAGCACAGGGCACCUGAGAAAGGAGGGGCCCCUCUGCCUUUACUCUGUCUCCCACUAGAGGCAGCUGGUUCCUUCAGGGAACUCUGGUGGGGGGUGAGGGGGUGGCUGGUUCUCAGUGGGCAGGGGUGACCCUACUGGGGUCAGUGGGCUGGCAAUGCUGGUCUUCACUAAGAAGAGUUGAAAAUAGCCAGGAAGCUAAGCCCUGGCUCCUGGGCUCCUGGGCAGAUGCUUAAUUAGGAGGAAGAAGGAACCAAAAUCAUGAACACAACUGGCUCUCUCAGGGGGAGGCUGUCACCCUCCAAGCUCUUCUUCCCCUUCCUCAAAUGGAGAUUCACACUCAUCCCUAGUUCAGGAGAGCCGCCAUUGAUGAUGAGGAAAUCCGUGUCAAAGAAGCUGGAAAGACUGCUAUUCAUUGUGAGAAUUUUGUUUCCACUGCUACAUUACAUUGUUUCUUCUUGUUUUCCCUUCCAAUUUCCAGUUAAGAAUCUUUCACAGAAAAUUUUUAAUUUUAUCACAAACUGCACAGAUAUCACACAGCUGCACCCCCAUUUGGUGACACAAAGCAUACCCUUCUGUGAAGAUUUUCACUUUACGCCAAGGCAUGAUUGUCACUUUACGCCAAGGCAAUAAAUUUUUACAAAUUUUGUAUAACAGGAGCUGAAUUCUGGGUUCUCAAAUGUGAAAUGUGGCAAAAAAAAAAAAAAAAAAAAAAAAGAUUUAAUUCAAGCAUUUUGUCAUGUGGUUCUUAUUUCUUCAACCAAGUUUGUUUACAGUCACUGCCUUUGAAAUACAGUCAAAUACAUCUG